GACCACAGAGGCAGAGGGGUGGGCGGGCUGGCCCAUGGCUGAGACCUCUCUCCCAGAGCUGGGGGGAGAGGACAAAGCCACGCCUUGCCCCAGCAUCCUGGAGCUGGAGGAGCUCCUGCGGGCAGGGAAGUCUUCUUGCAGCCGUGUGGACGAAGUUUGGCCCAACCUUUUCAUAGGAGAUGCGGCCACGGCAAACAACCGCUUUGAGCUGUGGAAGCUGGGCAUCACCCACGUGCUGAACGCCGCCCACAAGGGCCUCUACUGUCAGGGCGGCCCUGACUUCUACGGCAGCAGUGUGAGCUACCUGGGGGUGCCAGCCCACGACCUCCCUGAUUUUGACAUCAGUGCCUACUUCUCCUCUGCGGCUGACUUCAUCCACCGUGCCCUCAACACGCCUGGGGAGCUGGUCCUUACUCCCUGCCAUGGGGCUCUGCCACUUUGCCACCCUGGCACUGAUCCUGCUGGUGCUGCUGGAGGCUCUGGCCCAGGCGGACACACAGAAGAUGGUGGAAGCCCAGCGUGGGGUCGGCCCUAGAGCCUGCUACUCCAUCUGGCUCCUCCUGGCGCCUACACCCCCUCUCAGCCACUGUCUUCAGUCUCCACAGAAACAGCAUCAAGUGUGCGGAGACAGGCGGCUGAAAGCCAGCAGCACGAACUGCCCGUCAGAGAAGUGCACAGCCUGGGCCAGAUACUCCCACAGGAUGGACUCACUGCAGAAGCAGGACCUCCGGAGGCCCAAGAUCCAUGGGGCAGUCCAGGCAUCUCCCUACCAGCCGCCCACAUUGGCUUCGCUGCAGCGCUUGCUGUGGGUCCGUCAGGCUGCCACACUGAACCAUAUCGAUGAGGUCUGGCCCAGCCUCUUCCUGGGAGAUGCGUACGCAGCCCGGGACAAGAGCAAGCUGAUCCAGCUGGGAAUCACCCACGUUGUGAAUGCCGCUGCAGGCAAGUUCCAGGUGGACACAGGUGCCAAAUUCUACCGUGGAAUGUCCCUGGAGUACUAUGGCAUCGAGGCGGACGACAACCCCUUCUUCGACCUCAGUGUCUACUUUCUGCCUGUUGCUCGAUACAUCCGAGCUGCCCUCAGUGUUCCCCAAGGCCGCGUGCUGGUACACUGUGCCAUGGGGGUAAGCCGCUCUGCCACACUUGUCCUGGCCUUCCUCAUGAUCUGUGAGAACAUGACGCUGGUAGAGGCCAUCCAGACGGUGCAGGCCCACCGCAAUAUCUGCCCUAACUCAGGCUUCCUCCGGCAGCUCCAGGUUCUGGACAACCGACUGGGGCGGGAGACGGGGCGGUUCUGAUCUGGCAGGCAGCCAGGAUCCCUGACCCUUGGCCCAACCCCACCAGCCUGGCCCUGGGAACAGCAGGCUCUGCUGUUUCUAGUGACCCUGAGAUGUAAACAGCAAGUGGGGGCUGAGGCAGAGGCAGGGAUAGCUGGGUGGUGACCUCUUAGCGGGUGGAUUUCCCUGACCCAAUUCAGAGAUUCUUUAUGCAAAAGUGAGUUCAGUCCAUCUCUAUAAUAAAAUAUUCAUCGUCAUAAA